AGGCCGCGCUCAGCAGGCGGGGCGGGAGCCGCGUGCGCCCGAGGACCCGGCCGGAAGGCUUGCGCCAGCUCAGGAUGAGGACAGGCUGGGCGACCCCUCGCCGCCCGGCGGGGCUCCUCAUGCUGCUCUUCUGGUUCUUCGAUCUCGCGGAGCCCUCUGGCCGCGCAGCUAAUGACCCCUUCACCAUCGUCCAUGGAAAUACGGGCAAGUGCAUCAAGCCAGUGUAUGGCUGGAUAGUAGCAGACGACUGUGAUGAAACUGAGGACAAGUUAUGGAAGUGGGUGUCCCAGCAUCGGCUCUUUCAUUUGCACUCCCAAAAGUGCCUUGGCCUCGAUAUUACCAAAUCGGUAAAUGAGCUGAGAAUGUUCAGCUGUGACUCCAGUGCCAUGCUGUGGUGGAAAUGUGAGCACCACUCUCUGUACGGAGCUGCCCGGUACCGGCUGGCUCUGAAGGAUGGACAUGGCACAGCAAUCUCAAAUGCAUCUGAUGUCUGGAAGAAAGGAGGCUCAGAGGAAAGCCUUUGUGACCAGCCUUAUCAUGAGAUCUAUACCAGAGAUGGGAACUCUUAUGGGAGACCUUGUGAAUUUCCAUUCUUAAUUGAUGGGACCUGGCAUCAUGAUUGCAUUCUUGAUGAAGAUCAUAGUGGGCCAUGGUGUGCCACCACCUUAAAUUAUGAAUAUGACCGAAAGUGGGGCAUCUGCUUAAAGCCUGAAAACGGUUGUGAAGAUAAUUGGGAAAAGAACGAGCAGUUUGGAAGUUGCUACCAAUUUAAUACUCAGACGGCUCUUUCUUGGAAAGAAGCUUAUGUUUCAUGUCAGAAUCAAGGAGCUGAUUUACUGAGCAUCAACAGUGCUGCUGAAUUAACUUACCUUAAAGAAAAAGAAGGCAUUGCUAAGAUUUUCUGGAUUGGUUUAAAUCAGCUAUACUCUGCUAGAGGCUGGGAAUGGUCAGACCACAAACCAUUAAACUUUCUCAACUGGGAUCCAGACAGGCCCAGUGCACCUACUAUAGGUGGCUCCAGCUGUGCAAGAAUGGAUGCUGAGUCUGGUCUGUGGCAGAGCUUUUCCUGUGAAGCUCAACUGCCCUAUGUCUGCAGGAAACCAUUAAAUAAUACAGUGGAGUUAACAGAUGUCUGGACAUACUCAGAUACCCGCUGUGAUGCAGGCUGGCUGCCAAAUAAUGGAUUUUGCUAUCUGCUGGUAAAUGAAAGUAAUUCCUGGGAUAAGGCACAUGCGAAAUGCAAAGCCUUCAGUAGUGACCUAAUCAGCAUUCAUUCUCUAGCAGAUGUGGAGGUGGUUGUCACAAAACUCCAUAAUGAGGAUAUCAAAGAAGAAGUGUGGAUAGGCCUUAAGAACAUAAACAUACCAACUUUAUUUCAGUGGUCAGAUGGUACUGAAGUUACUCUAACAUAUUGGGAUGAGAAUGAGCCAAAUGUUCCCUACAAUAAGACGCCCAACUGUGUUUCCUACUUAGGAGAGCUAGGUCAGUGGAAAGUCCAAUCAUGUGAGGAGAAACUAAAAUAUGUAUGCAAGAGAAAGGGAGAAAAACUGAAUGACGCAAGUUCUGAUAAGAUGUGUCCUCCAGAUGAGGGCUGGAAGAGACAUGGAGAAACCUGUUACAAGAUUUAUGAGGAUGAGGUCCCUUUUGGAACAAACUGCAAUCUGACUAUCACUAGCAGAUUUGAGCAAGAAUACCUAAAUGAUUUGAUGAAAAAGUAUGAUAAAUCUCUAAGAAAAUACUUCUGGACUGGCCUGAGAGAUGUAGAUUCUUGUGGAGAGUAUAACUGGGCAACUGUUGGUGGAAGAAGGCGGGCUGUAACCUUUUCCAACUGGAAUUUUCUUGAGCCAGCUUCCCCGGGCGGCUGCGUGGCUAUGUCUACUGGAAAGUCUGUUGGAAAGUGGGAGGUGAAGGACUGCAGAAGCUUCAAAGCACUUUCAAUUUGCAAGAAAAUGAGUGGACCCCUUGGGCCUGAAGAAGCAUCCCCUAAGCCUGAUGACCCCUGUCCUGAAGGCUGGCAGAGUUUCCCCGCAAGUCUUUCUUGUUAUAAGGUAUUCCAUGCAGAAAGAAUUGUAAGAAAGAGGAACUGGGAAGAAGCUGAACGAUUCUGCCAAGCCCUUGGAGCACACCUUUCUAGCUUCAGCCAUGUGGAUGAAAUAAAGGAAUUUCUUCACUUUUUAACGGACCAGUUCAGUGGCCAGCAUUGGCUGUGGAUUGGUUUGAAUAAAAGGAGCCCAGAUUUACAAGGAUCCUGGCAAUGGAGUGAUCGUACACCAGUGUCUACUAUUAUCAUGCCAAAUGAGUUUCAGCAGGAUUAUGACAUCAGAGACUGUGCUGCUGUCAAGGUAUUUCAUAGGCCAUGGCGAAGAGGCUGGCAUUUCUAUGAUGAUAGAGAAUUUAUUUAUUUGAGGCCUUUUGCUUGUGAUACAAAACUUGAAUGGGUGUGCCAAAUUCCAAAAGGCCGUACUCCAAAAACACCAGACUGGUACAAUCCAGACCGUGCUGGAAUUCAUGGACCUCCACUUAUAAUUGAAGGAAGUGAAUAUUGGUUUGUUGCUGAUCUUCACCUAAACUAUGAAGAAGCCGUCCUGUACUGUGCCAGCAAUCACAGCUUUCUUGCAACUAUAACAUCUUUUGUGGGACUAAAAGCCAUCAAAAACAAAAUAGCAAAUAUAUCUGGUGAUGGACAGAAGUGGUGGAUAAGAAUUAGCGAGUGGCCAAUAGAUGAUCAUUUUACAUACUCACGAUAUCCAUGGCACCGCUUUCCUGUGACAUUUGGAGAGGAAUGCUUGUACAUGUCUGCCAAGACUUGGCUUAUCGACUUAGGUAAACCAACAGACUGUAGUACCAAGUUGCCCUUCAUCUGUGAAAAAUAUAAUGUUUCUUCGUUAGAGAAAUACAGCCCAGAUUCUGCAGCUAAAGUGCAAUGUUCUGAGCAAUGGAUUCCUUUUCAGAAUAAGUGUUUUCUAAAGAUCAAACCCGUGUCUCUCACAUUUUCUCAAGCAAGCGAUACCUGUCACUCCUAUGGUGGCACCCUUCCUUCAGUGUUGAGCCAGAUUGAACAAGACUUUAUUACAUCCUUGCUUCCGGAUAUGGAAGCUACUUUAUGGAUUGGUUUGCGCUGGACUGCCUAUGAAAAGAUAAACAAAUGGACAGAUAACAGAGAGCUGACGUACAGUAACUUUCACCCAUUAUUGGUUAGUGGGAGGCUGAGAAUACCAGAAAAUUUUUUUGAGGAAGAGUCUCGCUACCACUGUGCCCUAAUACUCAACCUCCAAAAAUCACCGUUUACUGGGACGUGGAAUUUUACAUCCUGCAGUGAACGCCACUUUGUGUCUCUCUGUCAGAAAUAUUCAGAAGUUAAAAGCAGACAGACGUUGCAGAAUGCUUCAGAAACUGUAAAGUAUCUAAAUAAUCUGUACAAAAUAAUCCCAAAGACUCUGACUUGGCACAGUGCUAAAAGGGAGUGUCUGAAAAGUAACAUGCAGCUGGUGAGCAUCACGGACCCUUACCAGCAGGCAUUCCUCAGUGUGCAGGCGCUCCUUCACAACUCUUCCUUAUGGAUCGGACUCUUCAGUCAAGAUGAUGAACUCAACUUUGGUUGGUCAGAUGGGAAACGUCUUCAUUUUAGUCGCUGGGCUGAAACUAAUGGGCAACUCGAAGACUGUGUAGUAUUAGACACUGAUGGAUUCUGGAAAACAGUUGAUUGCAAUGACAAUCAACCAGGUGCUAUUUGCUACUAUUCAGGAAAUGAGACUGAAAAAGAGGUCAAACCAGUUGACAGUGUUAAAUGUCCAUCUCCUGUUCUAAAUACUCCGUGGAUACCAUUUCAGAACUGUUGCUACAAUUUCAUAAUAACAAAGAAUAGGCAUAUGGCAACAACACAGGAUGAAGUUCAUACUAAAUGCCAGAAACUGAAUCCAAAAUCACAUAUUCUGAGUAUUCGAGAUGAAAAGGAGAAUAACUUUGUUCUUGAGCAACUGCUGUACUUCAAUUAUAUGGCUUCAUGGGUCAUGUUAGGAAUAACUUAUAGAAAUAAGUCUCUUAUGUGGUUUGAUAAGACCCCACUGUCAUAUACACAUUGGAGAGCAGGAAGACCAACUAUAAAAAAUGAGAAGUUUUUGGCUGGUUUAAGUACUGACGGCUUCUGGGAUAUUCAAACCUUUAAAGUUAUUGAAGAAGCAGUUUAUUUUCACCAGCACAGCAUUCUUGCUUGUAAAAUUGAAAUGGUUGACUACAAAGAAGAAUAUAAUACUACACUGCCACAGUUUAUGCCAUAUGAAGAUGGUAUUUACAGUGUUAUUCAAAAAAAGGUAACAUGGUAUGAAGCAUUAAACAUGUGUUCUCAAAGUGGAGGUCACUUGGCAAGCGUUCACAACCAAAAUGGCCAGCUCUUUCUGGAAGAUAUUGUAAAACGUGAUGGAUUUCCACUAUGGGUUGGGCUCUCAAGUCAUGAUGGAAGUGAAUCAAGUUUUGAAUGGUCUGAUGGUAGUACAUUUGACUAUAUCCCAUGGAAAGGCCAAACAUCUCCUGGAAAUUGUGUUCUCUUGGAUCCAAAAGGAACUUGGAAACAUGAAAAAUGCAACUCUGUUAAGGAUGGUGCUAUUUGUUAUAAACCUACAAAAUCUAAAAAGCUGUCCCGUCUUACAUAUUCAUCAAGAUGUCCAGCAGCAAAAGAGAAUGGGUCACGGUGGAUCCAGUACAAGGGUCACUGUUACAAGUCUGAUCAGGCAUUGCACAGUUUUUCAGAGGCCAAAAAAUUGUGUUCAAAACAUGAUCACUCUGCAACUAUCGUUUCCAUAAAAGAUGAAGAUGAGAAUAAAUUUGUGAGCAGACUGAUGAGGGAAAAUAAUAACAUUACCAUGAGAGUUUGGCUUGGAUUAUCUCAACAUUCUGUUGACCAGUCUUGGAGUUGGUUAGAUGGAUCAGAAGUGACAUUUGUCAAAUGGGAAAAUAAAAGUAAGAGUGGUGUUGGAAGAUGUAGCAUGUUGAUAGCUUCAAAUGAAACUUGGAAAAAAGUUGAAUGUGAACAUGGUUUUGGAAGAGUUGUCUGCAAAGUGCCUCUGGACUGUCCUUCAUCUACUUGGAUUCAGUUCCAAGACAGUUGUUACAUUUUUCUCCAAGAAGCCAUCAAAGUAGAAAGCAUAGAGGAUGUCAGAAAUCAGUGUACUGACCAUGGAGCGGACAUGAUAAGCAUACAUAAUGAAGAAGAAAAUGCUUUUAUACUGGAUACUUUGAAAAAGCAAUGGAAAGGCCCAGAUGAUAUCCUACUAGGCAUGUUUUAUGACACAGAUGAUGCGAGUUUCAAGUGGUUUGAUAAUUCAAAUAUGACAUUUGAUAAGUGGACAGACCAAGAUGAUGAUGAGGAUUUAGUUGACACCUGUGCUUUUCUGCACAUCAAGACAGGUGAAUGGAAAAAAGGAAAUUGUGAAGUUUCUUCUGUGGAAGGAACACUAUGCAAAACAGCUAUCCCAUACAAAAGGAAAUAUUUAUCAGAUAACCACAUUUUAAUAUCAGCAUUGGUGAUUGCUAGCACGGUAAUUUUGACAGUUUUGGGAGCAAUCAUUUGGUUCCUGUACAAAAAACAUUCUGAUUCUCGUUUCACCACAGUUUUUUCAACCGCACCCCAAUCACCUUAUAAUGAAGACUGUGUUUUGGUAGUUGGAGAAGAAAAUGAAUAUCCUGUUCAAUUUGACUAAGUUUUUGGUAAUCUUGCACUAAGACAUCAACAAAAUGCCCUGGCAGAGAUAACUUGGGAAAGAUUUUAAUAUAAAACUUGACAUUGGAUAUUAGAGCUUUAAUGGUAUUCCUUAUUCCAGUAACAUUUUUAUGUACUCAUCUGCUGUGAAAAGUCUUUAGGUUCAUUAAAAAAACAGGUUUUAGAAAUGAUCUUAGAUCUAAUAUAGUGAUUUUAAGCAUCCCGUCAAAGGCAGAAUCUGUCACUUGAAUGAAGGAAAGCUUAAAGCCCAAGCAGAUAAAAAUAAAAGCCCAGCCUAUUUGUCUUGCCUGCUGUAUCUUCCCUAUUUAGUUGACCCACUUUAGUUUAUAUGUUUAUUAGUAAACAUGAAAUGGGGAAUAAGUGAUUUUAAGUACAUCCCAUACAUUUAAAUAUCUUUGAUAAUUGUUAUUUUUUUGGCAGAUAAUUCCUCUAGAAUGUGUAUCUUUUUAUGAUUUAGAUGAAGAAAAUUUUACAACUUUUAACACCCCACACCAAUUUUAGUUUCAUUACUUUUACACACACCAUUUUAUCACAAAUGACUCAAGUUUUAAUGAAUGUUUAUAAAUUAUUUGAAACAAAAUAUGAUCGCUGUGUCCAGGAUGGCAUAGAGAAAGCUGGCAAUUAGGUUAACACUUACAUAUUAUAGUGCCCCUUUAAGGAUUUCUCUCUUGCCACCAUACCUUUUGUACUUUCCCCUAUACAAGAUGUAUCUCAUUCUCCUCAAGCAUUUAUAAAUUUUUCCUUCAAUGACAUGAAAACUGUGCAAGCAAAAACCGAAGAAAAACACUUAAGUACAACUGUAGUGACAGUGAUCAAAGUUUUCAGUGCAUUUAUUGUACAUUUUAAGAAAAAGGUGAAAAUCAUUUGGGGAGUAAAAAAAUGAAAAAGCUGAAACGAGUAAUUUUCCUCACCAUCAAUAAACCAAAAACAGGAAAGAUAAAGAAUGUAUAAAUUUCACGUAAAUUAGUCACGUAUCACUUAUCAAUGGGGAUACGUUCUAAGAAAUGCAUAGUUAGGGAAUCUUGUGUGAAAAUCAGCUUGUAUUUACACAAACCCAGAUGGUAGAGCCUAUUUUGUCCCAAACCUACACAGCAUGUUACUGUGCUGAAUACUGCAGACAAUUGUAACACAAUAUUUGUGUAUCUAAAUAUAGAAAAGGUACAGUAAAAAUAUGGUCUACUAAGGAAACACUGUUCUAUAUGUGGUCCAUUACUGACUGAAGUAUACUGUCUAGAAGUCUGAGGCUCAAAGAAAAGUAAUCCCUCUUCUGAAUCCACACCCCAUCAAUUAUCUUACUUUCUUCUGGGGAGAUAGAUAGAUAUACUAUCUCACUAGCUUGACUAAUGGCAACAAAGUUCCAGCUUGUGUAGUCUCUUUUUAUUGACCACAUGAAUCGAAAACACUCAUCACAAUUAAUGGCACUAUCAUUAAUGAGACAUGAGUAACUAAAAAGUGAUAGAAAACUAUUAACAGUGCGGCUACAUGGUACUGAAAAUGCAGGCAUUACACCAGCUGUUACACAAGCACAAGCAUGCUCUGUAAGAGCUUUACAUUUCUGAGAUUUUGUAUAGUGAUUGAGAUGUCUAUUUUAUUAUUGAUAGACUAUUACUAAUGUCAAUAUUGAACACUACCCUGGAAUUCCUGCCUGGUUUUCCUACCCAAAUUGUACCACUCCUUGAAGAACUACAGGCACAGUAAAAAAAAUAUGGCGUAUUAUGUGAACUAAAAGAGUUCUAAAGGAGUUCUUAAAGGAGUGGUAGAAUUUGGGUAGGAAAGUGAUUAAGUCCAACUUAAAACCAACAGUCUCAAACGUCUACAACUACAAUGUCCAAUGAGCCACUAGCCACAUGAGGCUAUUUAAGUAAAUUUAGUUUAAAAUCCAGUUUUCGAAUUACAUUAGCCACAUUGUCAAGUGUUCAAAUCACAGGUGGUUAGUGGCUACUGUACUGGGCAACAUACAUUAUAGAACAUUUUCAUUAUAGGAAGUUUUAUUGGGCAGUGCUGCUCUUAAAUCCUACCUUCCACUCAACUCCCAUACAACUUUCUUUUGUACAUUUUGAUACUUUCUACCUAAUGGCAGCUCUUCCAAAAUAGCUGCUUUAAACUCUGAUUUAAUUUUCAAUAUUUGGUUUCAUUUUUCAACAGGCCAAGAGGCCUCUGGUAAUGAAGUGCUAUAUAUAUAUAUAUGAUGGAGUCUCACUGUGCUGCCCAGGCUACAGUGCAGUGGCUCGAUCUUGGCUCUCUCCAAUCUCCGCCUUGCAGGUUUUCAAGCAAUUCUCCUGCCUCAGCCUCCUUAGUAGCUGGGACCACAGACAUCUGUCACCACACCCAGCUAACUUUUUGUAUUUUUGGUAGAGACGGGGUUUCGCCAUAUUGACUGGGCUGGUCUCAAACUCCUGACCUCAAGUGAUCCACCCACCUUGGUCUCCCAAAGUGCUGGGAUUACAUGCGUGAGCCACCACACUUGGCCUACAUUUUUUCUUUAUAUACCAGAACAUCUAUAACAGGCACCUUAUCUACUCAUUAGUGAAGAGAUAAUUGGAUUACACAGGCAGGCUUGUUUACUACAUCCAGAAUGUAGAAACUGCUUUCUUCAACAUCUUGGUUCUAGCUAGUAAUAACAAUAUAAUUCUUUGGCAGAUAUUCAGAAUAACAUUUUAAACUACAUUUUCUUAGAAAAUUGCAUUCUUGUAGUGAGCAGUGUAUGGUCUCUUUUGUUCAGAAUUUAAAACUGAUAACCAAUGAAAGCCUUUUCUCUUAUUCCUCUACCGUCAUUUACAUGAUAAUCUGAAGCUAAUAUGACAAUAUUUAAAUACUAAGUGGUACUAGGGAACUACAAGAAUACUGUAAAGCUUAAGCCAUUGUUAUCACUGUCAUUUAGCAUUUAAUAACAAAACUAUACAGAAUUAUGUGCAUACCAAUGAAUGUUUUGUACCAUCUAGUUAAAUUUUUUAAAUAAAGUUUUAUGGGUUAAGCAGAAGACAACUGUCAUACUGAAUUUUAUUAAAAGUAUAUAUACUUCAAAUUCAAAGCAUCCCUUAGGACCCACAGAAUAUAUUAAAACUACCACCCUUAAAUUUUAUAUUUUUGCUUUAAGACAGACAAUGCAAAGGUAACUGGCAAGAGGUGAGCAAAUGUUUUAGAACAUUUAUAUUAUUGCUUAAAAUGAGAUUUGAAAUUGUAAUAAAAUUCUUGGUUAUGAA